AUAAACUUCGCCUUAAUUUUAAUAAUCAACACCCUCCUAGCCUUACUACUAAUAAUUAUUACAUUUUGACUACCACAACUCAACGGCUACAUAGAAAAAUCCACCCCUUACGAGUGCGGCUUCGACCCUAUAUCCCCCGCCCGCGUCCCUUUCUCCAUAAAAUUCUUCUUAGUAGCUAUUACCUUCUUAUUAUUUGAUCUAGAAAUUGCCCUCCUUUUACCCCUACCAUGAGCCCUACAAACAACUAACCUGCCACUAAUAGUUAUGUCAUCCCUCUUAUUAAUCAUCAUCCUAGCCCUAAGUCUGGCCUAUGAGUGACUACAAAAAGGAUUAGACUGAACCGAAU